GUAAUCAUUACCAAAUGAGGAGGAAAGGACGAUGUCAUCGAGGCUCUGCAGCGAGGCAUCCUUCUUCCCCAUGCAGUGUUAAACACUCCCCUACGCGAGAAACGCUGACCUACGCUCAAGCUCAAAGGAUGGUAGAGAUAGAAAUUGAAGGGCGCUUGCACAGGAUCAGUAUUUUUGAUCCCCUGGAGAUCAUAUUGGAAGAUGACCUCACUGCUCAAGAGAUGAGUGAGUGCAACAGCAACAAGGAAAACAGCGAGCGGCCUCCUGUCUGCUUAAGAACUAAGCGUCACAAAAACAACAGAGUCAAAAAGAAAAACGAGGCCCUCCCCAGCGCCCACGGCACGCCGGCCUCGGCCAGUGCCCUCCCGGAGCCCAAGGUGCGCAUCGUGGAGUACAGCCCUCCGUCCGCCCCCAGGAGGCCUCCUGUGUACUACAAGUUCAUCGAGAAGUCGGCCGAGGAACUGGACAACGAGGUGGAGUAUGACAUGGACGAGGAGGACUAUGCCUGGCUGGAGAUCGUCAAUGAGAAGCGCAAGGGCGACUGCGUCCCCGCCGUGUCGCAGAGCAUGUUUGAGUUCCUGAUGGACCGCUUCGAGAAGGAGUCGCACUGCGAGAACCAGAAGCAGGGCGAGCAGCAGUCUCUGAUCGACGAGGACGCCGUGUGCUGCAUCUGCAUGGACGGGGAGUGUCAGAACAGCAACGUGAUCCUCUUCUGCGACAUGUGCAACCUGGCCGUGCACCAGGAGUGCUACGGGGUGCCCUACAUCCCCGAGGGCCAGUGGCUCUGCCGCCACUGCCUGCAGUCGCGGGCCCGGCCCGCCGACUGUGUGCUGUGCCCCAACAAGGGUGGUGCCUUCAAAAAGACAGAUGACGACCGCUGGGGUCACGUGGUGUGUGCCCUGUGGAUCCCAGAGGUCGGCUUUGCCAACACGGUGUUCAUCGAGCCCAUCGAUGGGGUGAGGAACAUCCCUCCAGCCCGGUGGAAACUGACAUGCUACCUCUGUAAGCAGAAGGGCGUGGGUGCCUGCAUCCAGUGCCACAAAGCAAACUGCUACACAGCAUUCCAUGUGACGUGUGCCCAGAAGGCUGGCCUGUACAUGAAAAUGGAGCCCGUGAAGGAACUGACUGGCGGUGGCACCACCUUCUCCGUCAGAAAGACCGCUUACUGUGAUGUCCACACGCCUCCAGGCUGCACCCGGAGGCCUCUGAAUAUUUACGGGGAUGUCGAAAUGAAAAAUGGCGUCUGUCGAAAAGAGAGCUCGGUUAAAACGGUCAGGUCCACAUCCAAGGUCAGGAAGAAGGCAAAAAAGGCUAAGAAAGCUCUGGCUGAGCCCUGCGCGGUCCUGCCGACCGUGUGCGCUCCUUAUAUUCCCCCGCAGAGGUUCAUCAGAAUGCAAAGUAGAAAGUGUCUUAAAAGAGACUGUGAUCAGCAGGCAGACGGCCUGUGUCGGUUUGGUUCCUUUGACUGCUUCAGAUCUUCUAGGAGGAGCUCCUCUACUACGAGAGCCUGGACUUCAGCCUCACGGACAAGAACCUCAGAUAGGUUAAAUAGGAUUGCGAAUCAGGUGGCCAUUCAGCGGAAGAAGCAGUUUGUGGAGCGAGCCCACAGCUACUGGCUGCUCAAGCGGCUGUCCAGGAACGGGGCCCCCCUGCUGCGGCGGCUGCAGUCCAGCCUGCAGUCUCAGCGAAGCUCACAGCAGAGAGAAAAUGAUGAGGAGAUGAAGGCUGCCAAAGAGAAGCUGAAGUACUGGCAGCGGCUGCGGCACGACCUGGAGCGCGCUCGCCUGCUGAUCGAGCUGCUGCGCAAGCGGGAGAAGCUCAAGCGUGAGCAGGUGAAGGUGGAGCAGGUCGCCAUGGAGCUGCGGCUGACCCCGCUGACGGUGCUGCUGCGCUCAGUGCUGGACCAGCUGCAAGACAAGGACCCCGCCAGGAUAUUUGCGCAGCCCGUGAGUCUGAAGGAGGUACCAGAUUAUUUGGAUCACAUUAAACAUCCCAUGGACUUUGCCACAAUGAGGAAACGGUUAGAAGCUCAAGGGUAUAAAAACCUCCAUGAGUUUGAGGAGGAUUUUGAUCUCAUUAUAGAUAACUGCAUGAAGUACAAUGCCAGGGACACCGUGUUCUAUAGAGCCGCGGUGAGGCUGCGCGAUCAGGGAGGUGUUGUUCUGAGGCAGGCCCGGCGCGAGGUGGACAGCAUCGGCUUGGAAGAGGCCUCGGGGAUGCACCUGCCUGAGCGGCCUGCUGCGGCACCGCGGCGGCCUUUCUCCUGGGAAGACGUGGACAGGUUGCUGGACCCCGCCAACAGAGCCCACCUGGGCCUGGAGGAGCAGCUGAGAGAGCUGCUGGACAUGCUCGACCUCACCUGCGCUAUGAAGUCCAGCGGCUCCCGGAGCAAGCGGGCAAAGCUGCUCAAAAAGGAAAUUGCCCUUCUCCGAAACAAGCUGAGCCAGCAGCACAGCCAGCCCCUGCCCACGGGGCCAGGCUUGGAAGGCUUCGAAGAGGACGGAGCUGCGCUGGGGCCGGAGGCGGGCGAGGAAGGAGAUAAAUCUCCCCCUAAACUUGAACCAUCAGAUGCAUUACCUCUUCCUUCAAACUCGGAGACUAAUUCAGAACCACCAACCCUCAAACCAGUAGAACUCAACCCAGAGCAGAGUAAACUUUUCAAAAGAGUCACAUUUGAUAAUGAAUCACAUAGCGCUUGCACUCAGAGCGCACUGGUAAGCGGACGCCCUCCAGAGCCCACCCGCGCCAGUAGUGGCGAUGUGCCGGCGGCGGCGGCCUCCGCGGUGGCGGAGCCAGCAAGCGAUGUAAACAGACGCACUUCUGUUCUCUUCUGCAAAUCGAAAAGUGUAAGCCCCCCAAAGUCUGCCAAGAACACUGAAACCCAGCCAACUUCUCCUCAGCUAGGGACCAAAACCUUUUUGUCUGUAGUCCUUCCGAGGUUGGAGACUCUUCUGCAGCCAAGGAAAAGGUCGCGGAGCACAUGCGGAGACUCCGAGGUGGAGGAGGAGUCCCCAGGAAAGCGCCUGGACGCAGGUUCUCACUUUAACCACUAAUGUGCUGGGUAGUUCACUCUUUGGACCCUAAUCAUUUUCUCUUACCUCAACUUGGACUGGAGUUCUGCUAAGCGGCCGUUUUGGAAUGCACAAAGAUCACUGCAUCUUGCCUUUCACUUAAUUCUUGCGGAUCACAUUGGAAUCAUCAGCUCAAACAUCCUCUAGACAAAAUCACAAACAGCAGCCCUGGAGGAGCUCUCCCCCACCCCAGCCCACCCCCUCUGUAAGUCAGAGCCCGGCAGUGGGAAUGGUGCUGGCGCCCGGUGCACGCCUGGAGCUGGCGGGAUGUCGUGGCACCUCAGCCUUCCCUCUGGACAGUCACGAAGGACGCAGAGGAGAGCCCGGCACCGACUGGGAGCCUGCUGCAGCUGACGACACAGUGGACAGCAUUCUGAGGCUGUCCUGAGCAUGUGCGGAGCCGUCCCAUAGUGACUGGUGGUUUGGGUGUGACGGCCAUGCCCAGGCGCGUUGUGCUGUGUCUGUGCCAUGGGGUAUGGAGGAACUUGGCUCGGCACUGUCUGAGGAUGUGGCAUGGACAGUGCGUGCUCACUCACUCGCUAGCAUCUUCUGUAUUUCUGGGUUUUCUACCUGAUUUCCUUCUCCCCUUACUUCCCCUUCCUCUGUUUUUUCCCCACAAUGCCCAGUGGAUUCUUGAGCAGUGCUGCUGUUUGUCUCUUGCUGGUCACCACGCUGAGUGCCCCUGCGGCCAACUGAGAAGUCCUGCUCGUGGGGUGGGGCAUCUGUGCGUGGGAUCUUGUGCAGGCGUCUGUCCUGGGCCUUGGGUCUGUCUCUGACCAUCCCAGCUGCAUUGUCAUGGAGCUGGGUCCCAGCAAGAGCAGGUCUCGUGCAGGCGUCUGGCCUGGGCCUUGGUUCUGUCUCUGACCAUCCCAGCUGCAUUGUCACGGAGCGAGUCCCAGCACGAUGGGCCUUGGGUCUGUCUCUGACCGUCCCAGCUGCAUUGUCAUGGAGCAGGUCCCAGCAAGAUGGGCUUUGGGUCUGUCUCUGACUGUCCCCAGCGGCAUUGUCACAGAGCAAGUCUUGUGCAGGCAUCUGGCCUGGGCCUUGGGUCUGUCUCUGACCAUCCCAGCUGCAUUGUCGCGGAGCGGGUCCCAGCACGAUGGGCCUUGGGUCUGUCUCUGACCGUCCCAGCUGCAUUGUCAUGGAGCAGGUCCCAGCAAGAUGGGCUUUGGGUCUGUCUCUGACUGUCCCCAGCGGCAUUGUCACAGAGCAAGUCUUGUGCAGGCAUCUGGCCUGGGCCUUGGGUCUGUCUCUGACCAUCCCAGCUGCAUUGUCGCGGAGUGGGUCCCAGCAAGAGCAGGUCUCGUGCAGGCGUCUGGCCUGGGCCUUGGUUCUGUCUCUGACCAUCCCAGCUGCAUUGUCACGGAGCGAGUCCCAGCACGAUGGGCCUUGGGUCUGUCUCUGACCGUCCCAGCUGCAUUGUCAUGGAGCAGGUCCCAGCAAGAUGGGCCUUGGGUCUGUCUCUGACUGUCCCCAGCGGCAUUGUCACAGAGCAAGUCUUGUGCAGGCAUCUGGCCUGGGCCUUGGGUCUGUCUCUGACCAUCCCAGCUGCAUUGUCGCGGAGUGGGUCCCAGCAAGAUGGGCCUUGGGUCUGUUUCUGACCAUCCCCGGCUGCAUUGUCACGGAGCAGGUCCCAGCAAGAGCAGGUCUCGUGCAGGCGUCUGGCCUGGGCCUUGGUUCUGUCUCUGACCAUCCCAGCUGCAUUGUCACGGAGCGGGUCCCAGCAACAUGGGCCUUGGGUCUGUCUCUGACCGUCCCCGGCUGCAUUGUCACGGAGCAGGUCCCAGCAAGAGCAGGUCUCGUGCAGGCGUCUGGCCUGGGCCUUGGGUCUGUCUCUGACCGUCCCAGCUGCAUUGUCACGGAGCGGGUCCCAGCAACAUAGGCCUUGGGUCUGUCUCUGACCGUCCCCGGCUGCAUUGUCACGGAGCAAGUCUUGUGCAGGCAUCUGGCCUGGGCCUUGGGUCUGUCUCGGACCGUCCCGGCUGCAUUGUCACGGAGCAGGUCCCAGCAACAUGGGCCUUGGGUCGGUCUCUGACCGUCCCCGGCUGCAUUGUCACGGAGCAGGUCCCAGCAAGAGCAGGGUGCUGUUGGAAUCUUCUUCCGUGUGUGUUUUUGUUGAGAGGUUGAAAAAUGCACCAAAACUGCUCUUCUUUUAACGAUGGUAAAAGUGAAACUGAAAACAGGAGAUAGUGGGCUCUCCUUUGUCACUGCGUGGGGCCCUCAGGGCUCUGGUCUUCAGGGUGCAGGCUCAGCCCACCUGCUUCAUACGGCCAAGCUUCCCAUGAGCCGGAGAAGCCGAGGUGGCAGCUUGGGUGCCAGCGGCAGGGGCGGGCAGGGGCGGGCUUGUAUCCCGUGUUGUGGGGUUGCGUUCCCAUGGCUCCGUGCCCUCAGGUGUCUCGGCAGCCACUGAUCAGGGCCUGGUGUUCUUACACCUGUGGCCUGGAGGAUUUGUGGUGUCCACAUGGGUUGGGGGCUGGGAGCCUGAGACCAGAGGAGACUACGGCCCAUCAGUCAGACCUGCAGGCCUCCGCCUCCCCAGGUGGGCCCUGGGGCUUCUCUUCCCUGUGGGGAGGGGCGGUGUCUCAGCCGCUGUGGCCUUCAGUCUCUCAGAAGACCCUUUGGGGACCUCCCGGGACAGUUUCAGGUGUGCUGUGGACGUACCUGGUGACGGGCAGGCUUCCGGGGACUGCGCUUGGCUGGGCUGUGGGACACCUUUGCGCCAUCUCCUUUGGGGGCAGAGAGGGACAUUUCUGUGUUCAGUCUUUGGCCUCCUAGGAGGUCACUGGGAAGGCCCUUGAGGGUGGGUGGACCCUGGCCGCUGUGGGAAUUCCGUGCAGCUCCUGUGUUGAUGGGGCAGCGGCUCUUUCCUGGCAGCCGCCGCCUCUUUUAACGUAUUUCUCACAGUCACCAGCUUUACUUUCAGCGUUAAAAAAAAACCUCGUGCUGAAAAAGUUGCUGAAAGUUGCCCCUUGCUAUUUACAUGAUUUAGAGGCUUGGGCUCGGCCUCAGUGCCUGCUGUUUGCAAAUGCCUCAUGGACCGGGCACCCAUCUCUGCAGACCUUAGGCCCUGGGUUCCCCACGUUGGGCCCCACCUCAAGGCUGGCCUGGGCUUCAGAAUGUUCUGGGCUGAGGUCCUUGCAGGGGUGCUGAGGUGCGGGUCAUGGUGGACAUCUCCCAGCUGGCUGGAAGAGCCUCCCAGGGCGGGAGUUGGCAGGGCCGAGAUUGAGAGAUCUCAGAACCAUAGCUGUCUUAGAUUAUUUUCUGGUGGUCCAGGUGGAGGCUGGGAGGGUCCGGGCAGCGCAGGCCACCUUGCAGCUCCCCCGAGGUUCUGGGGACUCCAGGCGGUGGCUGCAGAGCCUCCCGGGAUGUGUCUGUGUCCUGGUCUGGCUUCUUGGCUUCCUGGGUGACCCCGCACUGCCGCAGCCCCCAGACCGCCUGUUAGCAAGCCUUGCAGCUGUCCCACCCCCGCCAGGCCUCCUGCUGGGUGGUGUCUCGGUUGGGCUGGGUUUGUCUGUGCUGCCCACGUCUUCCCGGGUGCUGUCACAUUUUCAUGGGUGACACGCAGAACCUCUGUGUGUUCUUGCGUCAUACGCGCACUCACUGAAUGCUUAGGAAAAUUAAGAGGGGCAUUUUAUCAUUCUCCUCUUUCUGAGAAUUAAGGACUUGCCUUGUGUUUUAAUCCCCUUCCUGGCCCCACUCCAUGCACACGGAGCCGGGGCCGUCGUGGCUGCUGAGUGGUCUGUGCAUGGCUUGGCUGUGUUGGUGCUGGCACAGCUGCGGGUGAUCUCGUGCUAGGGCCCUCAGGCUGGCACCUCUGGGCAGUCUUGUGAAGGCCGCACUGGUCAUCGUCUUCCCCCAAGUGGCCGUUGCUCGGCCAACCAGUAACUACUAAAAGCCUCCCCACCCAGGCCCUGGGCUGCGUCUGUUCAGCCUGGAGCAGGCUCACCCUGCACCUGGGGUCUGGAGUGUGCUGGGGGCCGGGCUGUGGGGUGUGGGUCGCCAGGCUCGUGGCUGCUCUCUGGAGACGGGUCACACGCGUUGGCAGACCCCUCUCCGGGCCUGUGGGCUGAAUGCUGGCAGGGGUGCUGGGCUCCGUCCGUCCACUGCUGAUGCGAGCUGGGUGGGCUUCCCUUGCCUUCACCCACUCAGGUUGGAGUAGGGAUGGAGUCGCUGCUCCUGAGGGGUUCUCGGGGGCCAGGACGGGACUUUUAAUUCCCUCUUGAGACAUCUUCGGGGCCUGAGUGUGCAGGGUCUGAGCCCACUCUGUGAUGAGUAUGGGGAGCAUGUGGAGCCCCAGGGCAGCUCAGCGUGUGGCUCAAGGCCUUCUCCUGUAGGUUUUUAAAUUUAUUUGUUCCCUUGCCAGAAAUGAGUAUGACACCCCCAACUGGCCACAGUUCCUGCCUUAAAAUGACCGAGGUUAAAAUGAGAAACACAGAGCUUCCCUUGGAGGUCACGGUACAUUCCAGUCCAGGAGAGACGGAGCCGGUGUCUGACUUGAGUCUGUGGAGGGCAGCAGUGCACCCGCCCAAUCUGUGCAUUCCCUUCUGAGCUUGAUUUAGCCCCUCUGUUUCAGUCAGUCAUGCUCAUUGAGAACAGACAGCAAGUGUAUGAAGCGGGUGGAGGCUGAUUCAGCCCCUGUAUUGAAAAGUCGGUCGUGCUCAUUGAGAACAGACGGGAAGCGUACGAAGCGGGUGGAAAAUCCCGCAGUCCAGCCAUUCCCUUCAAAACAUGCCUCCCAGCCACUCAGGAGGCUGAGGCAGGAGGAUCACUUGAGCCCAGGAGGUCAAGGUUGCAGUGAGCCAUGGAGUCCAUUGCACUCCAUCCUUGGUGACAGAGUGAGACAUCGUUUCCAAAAAAAUUCUACAGAAAUGCUCUAUUUACAAAUUUACAUAAUUUCCUUUGGAAAUAGAUUUAAAAAUUUUUUAAGGAUGAGGUAGGUAGGCAGGAAAACGGGGUUCUUUUUGGAUAAAAAAAUUCACAUGGCCGGGUGUCAUGGCUCAUGCCUGUAAUCCCAGCACUUUGGGAGGCCGAGGCAGGCGGAUCACGAGGUCAGGAGAUUGAGACCAUCCUGGCUAACACGGUGAAACUCCGUCUCUACUAAAAAUACAAAAAAUUAGCCAGGCAUGGUGGCGGGCGCCUGUAGUCCCAGCUACUCGGGAGGCUGAGGCAGGAGAAUGGCGUGAACCCGGGAGGUGGAGCUUGCAGUGAGCCAAGAUCGUGCCACUGCACUCCAGCCUGGGCGACAGAGUGAGACUCCGCCUCAAAAAAGAAAAAAAAAAUCACACACCCCUUUAGCUCUGACACCCAGAGGGCCCCCAGCAGGAACAUCAUCCCCCCGUUGUGACUCCCAUGGGGGACCUCAUCGGGGGGCCUUGGGCAGAUGUGUUGUUUCCCGUUGACUGACAAAGUCAGGAUUUUUAGGGGGAAAAUACUGAGAUUUGCCUUAUUUUUUAAACAUUGAGAUGAUGGAAUUGUGAGUGGUGUUUUGUUUAGCUGUGUACAGUACUUGCAGCUUCAUGGUGAGUGAGGCCAGACACACUCAGACACGGCGAUGGCCCCGGAUUUUGUGUUUUAAAGUGUUUCGUCAGCAUUUUUGACUUCAUGUUAACACUUGUCUUUUGAACCAAGGUUUUUUCUUUUUAAAACCUGAUUUCCUAUUCCCUGGAGCUCUGCUCCUGUGAACAUGUUUUUGUGUCUUUGGUGGCCCCUUCGGCCUGGUGAAGUUUCCGUUCAAACGCGGCCGGUGCCCACGUGGACAGGCCGCCCCCGUGUUUGCACUCACAGGUUGCACAUCUGCCCCCAUGGCAGGCUCACGGCAUCCUUUCUUUGCCU